AGAAGCUGCUGUAGCUUUAACCAGACAGCUCAGACCUGUCUGGAGGCUGCCAGUGACAGGUUAGGUUUAGGGCAGAGAAGAAGCAAGACCAUGGUGGGGAAGAUGUGGCCUGUGUUGUGGACACUCUGUGCAGAGCAUUUGGGAAAUAAAAGUACACAUAGAAGAAAUCUCAGAUUGCCCCACGAUCUCAGAAUCCACAGCUGCCAGUUUGAGAGCCUCCCUGCCCAUAGAGGAAGGACAAACCAACCUGCGUGUGUGAACUGCCUUCUUCUCCCUAGAGACCAGCACUUUCUCAACACCAGCACAUGUCAGGGUGACCGUCGAUGCCAUCUCUGUGGAAACUCCGCAGGACGUUCUUCGGGCUUCGCAGGGAAAGAGUGUCACCCUGCCCUGCACCUACCACACUUCCACCUCCAGUCGAGAGGGACUUAUUCAAUGGGAUAAGCUCCUCCUCACUCAUACGGAAAGGGUGGUCAUCUGGCCGUUUUCAAACAAAAACUACAUCCAUGGUGAGCUUUAUAAGAAUCGCGUCAGCAUAUCCAACAAUGCUGAGCAGUCCGAUGCCUCCAUCACCAUUGAUCAGCUGACCAUGGCUGACAACGGCACCUACGAGUGUUCUGUCUCGCUGAUGUCAGACCUGGAGGGCAACACCAAGUCACGUGUCCGCCUGUUGGUCCUCGUGCCACCCUCCAAACCAGAAUGCGGCAUCGAGGGAGAGACCAUAAUUGGGAACAACAUCCAGCUGACCUGCCAAUCAAAGGAGGGCUCACCAACCCCUCAGUACAGCUGGAAGAGGUACAACAUCCUGAAUCAGGAGCAGCCCCUGGCCCAGCCAGCCUCAGGUCAGCCUGUCUCCCUGAAGAAUAUCUCCACAGACACAUCGGGUUACUACAUCUGUACCUCCAGCAAUGAGGAGGGGACGCAGUUCUGCAACAUCACGGUGGCCGUCAGAUCUCCCUCCAUGAACGUGGCCCUGUAUGUGGGCAUCGCGGUGGGCGUGGUUGCAGCCCUCAUUAUCAUUGGCAUCAUCAUCUACUGCUGCUGCUGCCGAGGGAAGGACGACAACACUGAAGACAAGGAGGAUGCAAGGCCGAACCGGGAAGCCUAUGAGGAGCCACCAGAGCAGCUAAGAGAACUUUCCAGAGAGAGGGAGGAGGAGGAUGACUACAGGCAAGAAGAGCAGAGGAGCACUGGGCGUGAAUCCCCGGACCACCUCGACCAGUGACAGGCCAGCAGCAGAGGGCGGCGGAGGAAGGGUUAGGGGUUCAUUCUCCCGCUUCCUGGCCUCCCUUCUCCUUUCUAAGCCCUGUUCUCCUGUCCCUCCAUCCCAGACAUUGAUGGGGACAUUUCUUCCCCAGUGUCAGCUGUGGGGAACAUGGCUGGCCUGGUAAGGGGGUCCCUGUGCUGAUCCUGCUGACCUCACUGUCCUGUGAAGUAACCCCUCCUGGCUGUGACACCUGGUGCGGGCCUGGCCCUCACUCAAGACCAGGCUGCAGCCUCCACUUCCCUCGUAGUUGGCAGGAGCUCCUGGAAGCACAGCGCUGAGCAUGGGGCGCUCCCACUCAGAACUCUCCAGGGAGGCGAUGCCAGCCUUGGGGGGUGGGGGCUGUCCUGCUCACCUGUGUGCCCAGCACCUGGAGGGGCACCAGGUGGAGGGUUUGCACUCCACACAUCUUUCUUGAAUGAAUGAAAGAAUAAGUGAGUAUGCUUGGGCCCUGCAUUGGCCUGGCCUCCAGCUCCCACUCCCUUUCCAACCUCACUUCCCGUAGCUGCCAGUAUGUUCCAAACCCUCCUGGGAAGGCCACCUCCCACUCCUGCUGCACAGGCCCUGGGGAGCUUUUGCCCACACACUUUCCAUCUCUGCCUGUCAAUAUCGUACCUGUCCCUCCAGGCCCAUCUCAAAUCACAAGGAUUUCUCUAACCCUAUCCUAAUUGUCCACAUACGUGGAAACAAUCCUGUUACUCUGUCCCACGUCCAAUCAUGGGCCACAAGGCACAGUCUUCUGAGCGAGUGCUCUCACUGUAUUAGAGCGCCAGCUCCUUGGGGCAGGGCCUGGGCCUCAUGGCUUUUGCUUUCCCUGAAGCCCUAGUAGCUGGCGCCCAUCCUAGUGGGCACUUAAGCUUAAUUGGGGAAACUGCUUUGAUUGGUUGUGCCUUCCCUUCUCUGGUCUCCUUGAGAUGAUCGUAGACACAGGGAUGAUUCCCACCCAAACCCACGUAUUCAUUCAGUGAGUUAAACACGAAUUGAUUUAAAGUGAACACACACAAGGGAGCUUGCUUGCAGAUGGUCUGAGUUCUUGUGUCCUGGUAAUUCCUCUCCAGGCCAGAAUAAUUGGCAUGUCUCCUCAACCCACAUGGGGUUCCUGGUUGUUCCUGCAUCCCGAUACCUCAGCCCUGGCCCUGCCCAGCCCAUUUGGGCUCUGGUUUUCUGGUGGGGCUGUCCUGCUGCCCUCCCACAGCCUCCUUCUGUUUGUCGAGCAUUUCUUCUACUCUUGAGAGCUCAGGCAGCGUUAGGGCUGCUUAGGUCUCAUGGACCAGUGGCUGGUCUCACCCAACUGCAGUUUACUAUUGCUAUCUUUUCUGGAUGAUCAGAAAAAUAAUUCCAUAAAUCUAUUGUCUACUUGCGAUUUUUUAAAAAAUGUAUAUUUUUAUAUAUAUUGUUAAAUCCUUUGCUUCAUUCCAAAUGCUUUCAGUAAUAAUAAAAUUGUGGGUGGAAAUUCUUA